ACUCACAGCCCCAGGUGCUGCUGGAGGUGGGAGCCGCGGCGCCUCCUGGACACAGGCGGGGUAGUGGUUCCGAGUCACCGCAGCGGGAGACCUGGGUGGGGGAGGGAAGAAGCCGGAGCCGCCGCAAGCCACACGAAUUUUUACUUGUUCCUGCAAAGCUGCUGGAGCUCAGAAGCUGAUUCUAUCACAUUGUAAGAUGCCUUUGGAUAAUUCUACAGUCCUCUUAAAUGAAUCUUUAGAACUUGGCAAGUCUCACUAGAUACCUUCAAUCAUCAUUUUGAGCUCAAAGAAUUCUGAGACUUAUGGUUGGUCAUAUAGAAGAGUACCUUGAACCUAUAGUUUCCUGAAGAAUCAGUUUAAAAGAUCCAAGGAGUACAAAAGAUACUGGGGAUUCAGUGAUGAACAAGACAGAAGCUGUCCCUGCUGUCAUGAGAACCGCCUUCUAGAAGAAGAAUAAUACACAAGUGAGAAACACAAAUAAUACACAAGUGAGAAAUUUGUGGUUUGUACUGUGCAGAGAAUUAAAAUGGAUAAAUGGAUAGUGUAAGGCUGGGCACUGUAAGGCUUGUGCCUGUAAUCCUAGCAGUUUGGGAGGCUGAGGUGGGAGGAUUGUGUAAGCCUAGAAGUUUGAUACCAGCCUGGGCAACAUAGUGAGACCCCAUCUCCACCAAAAAUUUAGAAAUUAGCUGGGCAUGAUGACGUAUGCCUGUGAUCCCAGCUACUUGGGAGGCUGAGGCAGGAGGACUUGAGCCUAGGAGGUUGACGCUACAGUGAGCUGUGAUUGUGUCACUGCAUUCCAGCCUGGGAGACAGAGUGAGACCUUGUCUUACGUGUACAAAAAAAAGGAUAAUGUGGUAGAGACUGGUGACUGCUUUCAUUAGGCAGUCAGAGAUAGCCUAAUUGAAAAAGGGGAAUUUUAAUUGAGAUCGGAAUGGCAAAAGGAGCCAGCUGUGUGAAGAUCUGAGAGAAGAGCUUUAUAGAUAGUGAGAACAAGAAAGACAAUGAAAUGUUUGAGGAACAUAAAGAGCAUAAUGUGACUGGAAUACAGUAAAUGAUGGGGAGAAUAUAUGGAGAUCAGGUUGGGGGAAAAAACUGGGAGAGAAGCAAAUUUACAGAAGAAAGUUAAGUGUUCUGUUUUAAGUAUAUGACAUUUUGGACACCUUUAAAAUCUGUAGAAAUGUCUAAAAAGCAGUUGGAUAUCUGACUGCAUUUGACAAUCUAUUCUAGGGGUGUGGAUUUGGGAGUCAUUGGCAUGUAGAAGUGUGAUUUAUCUAGGAAGUGUAUACAGAUUUAGAAGGAUUCAGCCCUGGCACAUGCCAGUAUUAAUUAGAGGAGAAGGAGCAGCCAGCAAGAUGAGUACAAAAGCAGGAGAAUAUUCUGUCACUGGAAUCAAGAAAAGAAGGUAUUUAAUAAAUGCAGAAGUGGUCGUCUACAUCACAUAUUGCUUAACGGUCAAAUAGAGAAUAAAACAGCCAUUAGACUUGGCAAUAUGGAGAUUUGGGAUAACUAAUAAGAGUGAGCAAUUUGAGUGGAGUGGUGGGGAUGAAAGCCUAAUUAAGAGUGAUGAAAGAAUAUGGGAAACUGCUAGAGAUGGCAAACAAUACAAUUAAAUUUUAUUUUCUCUUGAAACCUCACUGAAGCUAAAGUAAGAAGAUUUUUACGAAAGACAUAACAGGACAGAGAGAAUGGAGAAGAAACAGUAGCAACAAAAUUUGGGACUGCAAAAGGGAGCAUAGUAACUUUCUUGCAAAUCCCAGGAUCCUAAGCCUGCUGUGGGAAAGCUGAAACAAACUUCUUGGCACUGUAGAACCUCUAUAAUUUUCAUGAAUUGAAAACUAUUUCUGGAAAUAGGAGUGAUGGUGGAACUAAAACAGGAUGAUUUGUUGCAAAUCUGUUUAAGGGGUAAUUAUAUUCCAUGGAUCCUUUUCUUAACUUUGGAACCAAGGCAGCCACCUUUUUCCUAUCUUAGCAGAAGUCUGGAGAUUUAUUCCCUAGUAAGGAUAAAAUAAAGGAGCCACAAACAUGGCUGAGAAUGGGGGUGACAUGUUAAAAAUAGAAGGGUUAAGAACCCAGGGUACCAGGUUUUUAUACUCUUCAGGCAAGAGUUGAGAAGAUACAUAAUUAUUUUCUCUGAAUUAUAAUCAUCUUAAAAGAUCUAAAGAUUCUGACAUUGAGAAUUCCCCAAAGAAAUAUUUCAACCUGAUAGCCCUACAGUAAAGUUAACAGUCAGCAAGCUGUAUCACACAGAGCUUCAGUUUUUUUAGCGCUUACCCUUAAAUGUGAGCUCAUGUUCAGAGAUCAGUAGACAGCUGAGGAAAAACCUCUUAUGUGCAAGACAAAGGCCAAACCAAAAGGUAAAACACCAAGUUAGGGGAAAUGGAGAGCAGUUAGGUGGGCGAAAAUUAAACACAAACCUUACAUAAAGGUAAGAGGGAUGCUAUAUCCAUGAAGUAUGAACGAGAAACAGUAAGAAAUGAAAUUAGAAAUGAAAAAUUCAUUGGAAAGGUUGAAAAAUAAAAUCUAUUGAAAGUAGAGCAAAGAGCCAAAGAAAUGGAAAAUGGUAGAGAAAAAAUAAGAAAAUUACAACUGUCCAGGAUCUCCAAUGUUCAAAUAAGUGCUCCAGAAGGAGAGAGAGGAAACAGAGGGGAAAAACAAAGAAUAGAGAACAACUCGAGAAAACUCUCCAGAAUUAGAGGACAUGAGUUACCAGUUAGGAAAAGCCUGUUGAGUGACCAGUACAGAUAUAAAAAGCCAAAACAGGGCACAUCACUGUUCAAUUUUAGAAAACAAGGGAGUUUCCAGAGUGAAAUAAAUAACAGGUCACAUCUAAAGGAUCAGUAAUCAGAAUGGCUUUGCACUUCUUGACACCACACUGGAAGCUAGAAGAUAGUGGAGUCUUCAGCAUUCAGAAGGAAAAGUGAUUUUCAACCAGGUAUUCAGUAUCCAACUAAACUGUUGAUUAAGGAUAGACUAAUGACAGUUUUAGACUUACGAAGCCUUAAAAAAUUUACCUGUCAUGUCCCCUUUCUUAGGCAGUUAUUGGAGGAAUUACUCAACAAAAAUAAAGAAGUAAACUAAAAAAGAUGAAGGCAUAGGAUACAAGUAACAGGGAAUAUGACCUAACUAGAGACCCAGGGAAUCACCAGGAUGAUGAUGAAUAAUGAUCACAAGAAGACAGCUUGUCCUCAGGAGAAGUACAAAUGUCUACUACAAGACGAAAACGUAGUAUGUUAUGUUGUUUACCGUAAGCUGUAGUAAAAUGAGCUCGAUUGUUGACAGAGAUGACAGUAGUAUUUUUGAUGGGUUGGUGGAAGAAGAUGACAAGGACAAAGCGAAAAGAGUAUCUAGAAACAAAUCUGAAAAGAAACGUAGAGAUCAAUUUAAUGUUCUCAUUAAAGAACUGGGAUCCAUGCUUCCUGGUAAUGCUAGAAAGAUGGACAAAUCUACUGUUCUGCAGAAAAGCAUUGAUUUUUUACGAAAACAUAAAGAAAUCACUGCACAGUCAGAUGCUAGUGAAAUUCGACAGGACUGGAAACCUACAUUCCUUAGUAAUGAAGAGUUUACACAAUUAAUGUUAGAGGCUCUUGAUGGUUUUUUUUUAGCAAUCAUGACAGAUGGAAGCAUAAUAUAUGUGUCUGAGAGUGUAACUUCAUUACUUGAACAUUUACCAUCUGAUCUUGUGGAUCAAAGUAUAUUUAAUUUUAUCCCAGAAGGGGAACAUUCAGAGGUUUAUAAAAUACUCUCUACUCAUCUGCUGGAAAGUGAUUCAUUAACCCCAGAAUAUUUAAAAUCAAAAAAUCAGUUAGAAUUCUGUUGUCACAUGCUGCGAGGAACAAUAGACCCAAAGGAGCCAUCUACCUAUGAAUAUGUAAAAUUUAUAGGAAAUUUCAAAUCUUUAAACAGUGUAUCCUCUUCAGCACACAAUGGUUUUGAAGGAACUAUACAACGCACACAUAGGCCAUCUUAUGAAGAUAGAGUUUGUUUUGUAGCUACUGUCAGGUUAGCUACACCUCAGUUCAUCAAGGAAAUGUGCACUGUUGAAGAACCCAAUGAAGAGUUUACAUCUAGACAUAGUUUAGAAUGGAAGUUUCUGUUUCUAGAUCACAGGGCACCACCCAUAAUAGGGUAUUUGCCAUUUGAAGUUCUGGGAACAUCAGGCUAUGAUUACUAUCAUGUGGAUGACCUAGAAAAUUUGGCAAAAUGUCAUGAGCACUUAAUGCAAUAUGGGAAAGGCAAAUCAUGUUAUUAUAGGUUCCUGACUAAGGGGCAACAGUGGAUUUGGCUUCAGACUCAUUAUUAUAUCACUUACCAUCAGUGGAAUUCAAGGCCAGAGUUUAUUGUUUGUACUCACACUGUAGUAAGUUAUGCAGAAGUUAGGGCUGAAAGACGACGAGAACUUGGCAUUGAAGAGUCUCUUCCUGAGACAGCUGCUGACAAAAGCCAAGAUUCUGGGUCAGAUAAUCGUAUAAACACAGUCAGUCUCAAGGAAGCAUUGGAAAGGUUUGAUCACAGCCCAACCCCUUCUGCCUCUUCUCGGAGUUCAAGAAAAUCAUCUCACACGGCCGUCUCAGACCCUUCCUCAACACCAACCAAGAUCCCGACGGAUACGAGCACUCCACCCAGGCAGCAUUUACCAGCUCAUGAGAAGAUGGUGCAAAGAAGGUCAUCAUUUAGUAGUCAGUCCAUAAAUUCCCAGUCUGUUGGUUCAUCAUUAACACAGCCAGUGAUGUCUCAAGCUACAAAUUUACCAAUUCCACAAGGCAUGUCCCAGUUUCAGUUUUCAGCUCAAUUAGGAGCCAUGCAACAUCUGAAAGACCAAUUGGAACAACGGACACGCAUGAUAGAAGCAAAUAUUCAUCGGCAACAAGAAGAACUAAGAAAAAUUCAAGAACAACUUCAGAUGGUCCAUGGUCAGGGGCUGCAGAUGUUUUUGCAACAAUCAAAUCCUGGGUUGAAUUUUGGUUCCGUUCAACUUUCUUCUGGAAAUUCAUCUAAUAUCCAGCAACUUGCACCUAUAAAUAUGCAAGGCCAAGUUGUUCCUACUAACCAGAUUCAAAGUGGAAUGAAUACUGGACACAUUGGCACAACUCAGCACAUGAUACAACAACAGACUUUACAGAGUACAUCAACUCAGAGUCAACAAAAUGUACUGAGUGGGCACAGUCAGCAAACAUCUCUACCCAGUCAGACACAGAGCACUCUUACAGCCCCACUGUAUAACACUAUGGUGAUUUCUCAGCCUGCAGCCGGAAGCAUGGUCCAGAUUCCAUCUAGUAUGCCACAAAACAGCACCCAGAGUGCUGCAGUAACUACAUUCACUCAGGACAGGCAGAUAAGAUUUUCUCAAGGUCAACAACUUGUGACCAAAUUAGUGACUGCUCCUGUAGCUUGUGGGGCAGUCAUGGUACCUAGUACUAUGCUUAUGGGCCAGGUGGUGACUGCAUAUCCUACUUUUGCUACACAACAGCAACAGUCACAGACAUUGUCAGUAACGCAGCAGCAGCAGCAGCAGAGCUCCCAGGAGCAGCAGCUCACUUCAGUUCAGCAACCAUCUCAGGCUCAGCUGACCCAGCCACCGCAACAAUUUUUACAGACUUCUAGGUUGCUCCAUGGGAAUCCCUCAACUCAACUCAUUCUCUCUGCUGCAUUUCCUCUACAACAGAGCACCUUCCCUCAGUCACAUCACCAGCAACAUCAGUCUCAGCAACAGCAGCAACUCAGCCGGCACAGGACUGACAGCUUGCCCGACCCUUCCAAGGUUCAACCACAGUAGCACACGUGCUUCCUCUCUUGACAUCAAGGGAGGAAGGGGAUGGCCCAUUAAGAGUUACUCAGAUGACCUGAGGAAAGGAGGGAAAGUUCCAGCAGUUUCAUGAGAUGCAGUAUUGAGUGUUCUAGUUCCUGGAAUUAGUUGGCAGAGAAAAUGCUGCCUAGUGCUACAGAUGUACAUUAAAUACCAGCCAGCAGGAGGUGAUCAUAGGGGCAUAGCCAGUUCUGACAGUGUUUUAGGUGCCUGGAUAUUUUUUGAUGGAAAAAGAAUAUAUUGCCAAAUAUUAAGAAGCUCAGCUAUGAAAUGACCUCCAGGGAAUCAGAAAGGCACUAAUGAUGUUAGUAACUUUUAGUGGUUCUGUGCCUCUUAUCAAGUGUUACAGAGGACAUACCACUGCCAUGUCAGGGGUUUGCUUACAGUGAUGCCAUGAAGACAGUCCAGUAGACUUGGUAGCGACCCCCUCCCCCAACCCCUCUCCCUUUUCAGAUAAUGAUGGAACAGUAAUUACUUUCAGAAUGUUGUGUGGGUUCAAAUUCUCUAUGUACAGAUGAUGUAAAAAUAUGUAUAUGUCUAGAUAAAAGGAGAGAAAGCAAAACAUUUUGUAUGCUGCAUGAAAGCGUUAUCUCUUCCUUACAGGUGUGAGCACCUUUCCUGAAAUUCUGACACCAUGUGCAAACUGAUCCAUCCUGUUUUUCCUUUUGUUUACAACACAGUAGUGUUCUGUUCACUUUUCCGGGGCACAAGUUUUUUUGUUCAUACUUUGGCUGUGAUGUCACAGUUUGUUCAGUGAGGUAUGAUGUGCUGCUGGGAAUGGAUUUUUUUUUUCAGGUUAAAUUAUUGAUACAACAGGAUUUUCAAGUUAUUCAGAAAUAUCCCUCAUUUCAUUAUUUUUCAAUUAUGUUUGAAAAUAGGAUUUGCACUGCUUUAUUUUAGGUGGCUGGGAGUUUUGAUUGCAUAUUUUGUUAUAGUUCAUAGUUGGAAAUAUUUGCGUAAAUGGUUUUCAACAAGCCUGAAAGUAAUUUCAAGAAUGUUUCAGUUAUAGAGGUAAAAUUUGCACACAAAACAUCUUAGGCACUUUUUAACAUUCUCAAUCAUGGGAAUUUUAACUUUUGGGAUUUGUUGAAAUCUUUUUUAUUAUCCUUCACAAUUUCAAUGCUUCUUUUAGUCAGAAAUGAUUCAGGGUUAUUUGAGGGGAAAAAACCCCAUAGUGCCUUGAUUUUAAUUCAGGUGAUAACUCACCAUCUUGAAGUCAUUGUCCGGUUUCCGUAGCAGUUUUGAAACCUUAGUACCUUUUUAACAGCAUGUGGGUGUCAGUGUCAUUAUUAGUCUCCUAAUAAGUUCCUCUGAAGACUGCUAUCAGUCUCUUGGACUGGAGGUACAAAUAAUUUAGAAAUAAAAGAUGAUAACCUAACACUAUCAUAGUUAUUAAUGUGAUCCUAAAAUUGUUUCCUAAAUCAGCAUUUUUCUUUAGUCAUUUAAGAAUUUACCAGAAAUAUUUGCUCAAUAUGAUCUUGAUAUUCCUACAAAGAAAAAAGAAGGGGUAGGGAUUUGGCUAUGCCUUCACUACAACAUUAGAAUAUUGUAACUCACAUGCCUUCUAAACGUGAACUAAGAUUUCCUUUGGCAAUAUCAUAUUCUAAAAGUAAUAAAUUCCAAUACAAGUUACAUACAUUUAAAAAACAUUUUACAGAUUUUAUGGUACUAAUGAAAUUUACAGUGAUAGAACAAAAGAGGAUUAGUAGAAAAUACAUUAUUAGAAUAUAAAAAAUGUUAUUACUGAGGAAAGGGAGGAGAGGACAAGUGUAAUAAAUCAAAAUUGACCUCAAAAGAAAAUGUGUAACAGAGUUGAGGUUGUUAAAACAGAAAAGGUUCUGAAUAAUGAAGAUUAACCUAAUGCAGAAUUGCUAGGUAAAGAGGUCAGGGGAAUGCUAAGCCAGUUCUUAAGACUUCUCUGUCCUCUGCUUUGCUGUUAUCCUUAAGGCAUAUACUUUGUCUUUCUGCAGAAAAUUCUACCUGGCUACAAUUACUUUGAACAUUAAUGUUGAAAAAGAAAACAACCAAAGAAAAUUGGUACUUACCCUUCUACAAAAGAAGUGUGACUAGAUAUCAAUCAGUAAUUAACAUAUCAAGGAGCUCUUCUAGCUAAAUGACCAUCCAGUAGAGAUUUCCCACAUUCCCAUGAAUAUCAAGAAUAGUUGUCAGAAUAUGUAUGUACCUGAGCAUAUGUACACAGACAAGGGGGAUGUUGUGGAAUAUGGCAAUAGCAUUGUUCUUCUCCCCUUUCAAAUUGCCUUUCUUGACCUUAUGCCAUUCCAUAUAUAUCUGAGUUGUGCCUCAUUUAUUUAUUGGCAAUACCUAGUGAUACGGAUUUAGCUAACAAAAGAUAUGAAGAACUAUUAUAUUGAGGCCUGUCCUCUACAUACCACACUUAAAAGAUGGUGAACUGUGAGUACUACUUAGGUUGACAGCAACAAAGCAUAAGACAAGCCCCAGGUAAACGUCUAAACUGUUUACUCACAUUGUCCUACUCCAGCCCCUUCAAUUAUUUCCCAUCUCCACAAAUAGUCGGGGGAAAAAAUUAAAAUUUUCCUUUAUGAUUCUUACUGUUCUUCGCAGCUCAUCUUUUCCUGCUUAGAAUUAACCAUUGCUAAUUUAAAGGAGCAGCUAGCUGCUUUUCUGUCAGUCUGAAGCGUAGUAGUGGAAGAGGUAGUAAGCACCAGCUGCCUCUUUGCUGCUUUGUUUUCCUCCUGAUUCUCUUAAAUUUGGGUUGCAAAGCUAUCCCGCCCCCCACCCUGCCCCAUGAAACUUGAGCAUUCAAAUGAAGAUUCAGCAGUGUCUGUUCUUCAUUUCUAUAGCCAAAGCUGUUAGUUAAAAUCCCAAAUCUAUAGCAUUUAAAGAUACCAAAUAGAAACACCUUCCAGCUUUAAAAAAAAAAAAAAAAAAGUCUUCCCUCUGCUUUAUUCUCACUUUCUUAAAAACACUUAUUCUGGGUGGUACUUUUUAGGUAAGAAACUACUGAGUUUCAGGAAAAAUGCUAGCUACUCUGCAGUUACCGUGCUUUGGACUUGCAGUUAUCAUAGUUUUGGGAGAGUCAGUAUUGUUUAACAAAUGCAAGUGAGAACUAGAAGGGUUAAUAAAGUUGCUCCUUAGAGUGGUGUCAAACCAGAACCGAGACACUUAAAAAGUACUUCAUUUUUUGAAUGGAAAAUAUUGGAGAAAAGUAUGGGAGAUGCAGGUAGCAUGUGAGUAAAUACUACGGUCUAGCCUUCGAGCAUCCCAAAUUCCGGGGGUAACUUGACAGUGCUGUGCUCUCCUUUGUCAUUUAUAUCUGGCUUAGGAAUGGAAUAGUAAUAACAAGAUGCCAGUGAUUUGGAAUAGUUUGUUAUAGAACAUUCAGUGCAAAAUAGUGAAAAUGUUUGGUCUUCAGAAGUGCUGUAGUUGUUGGUCAUUGCCUUAAAGCAGUCUGCUUGACGCUAGGAGCACUGAAGCAGUCCAGCUCCAUCAAGAGCACUGUUGAAGGGAGAAGAACCCUUGUUCAGGAAGCCUUAGAAAGGGAUCCUUAAAAUAGUACUCUACGCAGACAAGUGAAAAUUCUUUUAAACUGGAUAUUACUCAACAUGUUUUCAGAUGUUUCCACUACAUUGAGGCAAACUUUUUAAAAGUGGAAUGCAAAUAGCAUUUUACUUUAGUAUUUCUGCUUUUUUCUUUCUGUUUCUUUGGUAAUUGAAAGUUUGUUGAUGAAUAUUUGUGUAAAACGCAUUCAAGUCUAUAACCUUUCCAAUUACCUGUGGCCCUUAGUCCCACAGGAGUCCCUGUUGGAAGGGGGUAAACACUGGAUAUUAAUGUUGCUGAGUGAGUCUUUCUAGCCAGGACAAGCUGAUUGGAAUUUUUGAAUGGUAGAGAAGAAACAGCACAAAGGCACUUGCCAUUUUAAGUGUUUGGAGAAAGAGAACCUUUUAAGUUUGGAUUGGGUGAGCUUUCUUCUAAAAGGAGCUUCUGAAGUAAUUGCAAAGGAAUAGAAUCGACUAUUUUUAUAGUAUAUUUAAUAUAUUUGUAUAUAACUAUAAUAGGAACCCUCUACAUGCCUCCCACUUUUCUAAUUUACUUCCCCUUUUGCCAUAGCACUAGUAUAGCCUCAUCCGCAUGGGUAAUGUGCCUAUUGUCAGCCUACCAAAAGAUAGUGCUGCUGCUUUAUGAGACAGGUGAGAAGACCCAACUCUCAUGCCUGGGGAUCCUUUACGGAAGGAAUAGCACACACUUUUAAAACAACAUACCACAGUCUAAAAGCAUCAUUUUGAAAUGUAACAAGCACUUUAUUGCAAUUACUCAUUUUGAUAAAGUUUAUUCUUAGGCGUUAACCAUUUCUAAAGGAUCCCCAAAUCAUCACUUACUUAGGUGAAAUUAUAUAAAAUGACACAUUUCUGAGAAAUGUUUAGGUCCAGUGAACCGUAGUUGGUUUAUGGGAGUGAUUUCAAGAUAGCCAAAUGAACUUUGAUUUUUGUUUUGAAUGUGGUGGAGUCAAGAGAUUGUAGAUGCCUAGUUUGAUUUAAACACUAUUGUAAACCUAUCUUGCCUAUUGUGUGGACACCAAAAGAGACCAAUGAGCCUGUUUAUUUUUCAGAGGUCUAGGAAAAUUGCAUCCGUGUGAGUAGAUGUACAGAACUAAUCUAAAAGUGAUUGCUAGUAACAUUUUAGAAUAUAAUAAUUUCAAGAAUUAUUCUGAGUGUUUUAAAUGUGCCCUGAAAUGUUGGCAUGUCAUUUCAGCAUUUCCAUUUGAAUUGCUCUUGUAAUAUUUUUGCACAAAAAGGACUGAGAAAAAGAAUACUUUGGUUAAAGGAAAAAAAUAGUAUAAUUUGGUCUUUAAUUUUAAUGUCUCCUGUGGAAACACUGGGGAUGAAUUUUGUUGGCACAGUUAUUCAGGAUAUUUAAAACAGUGUUGAACAGUUCACAAGAAAUUAAGCAAACUUGGAUUUUAAAAAUUAAAAUACUUUCUUUCCAUGUGACUGUUUUGCAUAGUUUUUUCCCCCUAUGUCAUAACACUACAUUCCUUGUUUUUCUUAAAUAAAAUACUCUGCAGGUUUUGUUGUGAGUGUUUAUAACAGUAUUUUGUAAGCUGCCUGGGUUUCCUCAGGGAAACAUUAUUUAGUGGAAUAGGAUAUAGUUUAUGGAGAGACAACUAAGUGAAAUUCCAUCACCACCACCAGCAAACACUGAGGUGCUGCAUUAAGUGACAAUCAAACUAGUAAGUAUUUAUGAAAGAAUUUAGAAAGGGGUUCAAAGAAGCAAUUGCUUUUAAAGCAGUUCUCUGGGGUUCUUGAAUAAAAAUGGCUAAAUGUAUUUAUUUAUAUUUUAAAAUACCUGUGUGUUCUGUUUUCUCAUCAAAGUGAUUUCGGUGUCAUGUAUUUAAUGUGUGGUUUGUUUUGUUUUGCACCAUAUUCUUCUUAGGGAACUGGCUCUGAUUUGGGGUGCAGUCACCAACUCUCAUGAUAAUCUUUACGGACAGUCUGAAUCUACUUUACUUCAGGACGGCAGUGGAGGGGCCAACUCCAGAUGCCCCUGCACUUCCCUCCUCAAGUCAUCUAAGAAAGAAUUUUAGAAAUAACUCCUUUCAAAUCUGAUUCAUACAGUUCCAACCUUUUUCUAGUUUCACUUGCUGCCUUCUUUGUUUUAUGGGCACUUUUUGUGUGAUUACUUCCCCAACACAGUCAAAGGCCAGUAUGACAGAACCAAUGGCACAUGAUGCCUCUAUUUUGCCCAUUUGGGGAAAUGUUAGUAAAAGAAAUAGCAUCUUUUAAUGGCUGUCAUUAUCAUAUCCAUAUUAAAAUCCAUUUAAAGUUCUUAAAUUUGGCGGAAUAAUGUAUACAGGCUGUAAACUUCUACAAAAAAUGUUUGCUGUCUUUAAUAUGGUGUCAAGUUACUUGGUCCUUUGAAAACAAAACAAAACUUCCAUACACAGCACUGCCCAGUAAAGCAGUGUUGGAAUAUUGGAAACCUAGACAUUUGAGGAUCCUUCUUGCUCACAAGCAUUGGAACAGAAUCCUCCACUUUAGGACUCAGAGAAGCUAUGGAGUCCCACAGGCUAGGUAUAGCACACAACUUAGAGAACGGUAGUUAAAGCACGUCAACCACAAUUGAAUUUAAUGAUCUAAAAAAUAUUUCUUAACUCUGAGGGUUAAACUGAAGAUACGUUUUCAAAUAAAAGCUUUUAAAUUUCUUAGGAAACAAACUGUGACAUCGCUUUUAAAAAUGACAUUCAAAUGUUUAUAAUGUGUGUUUUUGAGUUGGCUUGGACUAGUGCAAGUUCACUGCUGGCAAUGGUUAUGCCAGUAGUUAAGUUAAAAUAAGUUGUUACCUUCAGAUUGAUGUCUUGUAUAACCAGACAAUCAUCUUCAAGCAAAAAAAUUGGCCAGGAAAUGUCUUUUUAAAAAAAAAAAAAAAAAAAAAGAUGUGUCAGCCAGAACAGUUACCAUUCAGACCAUACUGGAAUGAUUUUGAAAUCUUUACUAUGGUUUAAGUUGGGGAAGGCCUCAGUAUGGCAUUUUCAUAUUCACUCUAUGUAAAGAUUGAAGCCCAAAGAUGAGUUAAAUUCAGUGCUGUAUUGAAACCAGUCAGUGCAAAAAAAAAAAAAAAGUUUUACCUUUGUAAAUUUUUCAUUGUUAACAUCAGUUGGUAGUUGUUAAAACAUGCACCAAAUUCUUUAUAAUGUUCUGUGUGGUUCUCAAUGUGAUAUUCUUGACAUUGCUGUCCUUACUGCUUGGUUCUUGGUUUUAAAUUAAAAAGUAGAUGUAGCUCAUCAUUUUUACUUCCAAAACGGUGGAGCUAAAAACGGCUAAUUGAUCUUGAGAUAAGAAUACCCUUUACUAAGGCAAAGAUUUAAUUGAAAUCCAAAAUGAUUUAUAGAAACGAAAGGCAUUUUCCAUUUGUUGUCUUCUGCCGAAAUUCUGAAUUGCAUACACACAUGAAGGAUAAUGAAUGGUUUCAACGGUGCUAUAUUAGGUUCUCUGAUUUUCAUGACCUAUGUAUGUUUGGAAAUACAAUAUUGUAUAAAAUGUGGAUCGUUUUGUUACCGAUUUAAUAUUGCCAUUUUAAUUUGGUGUAACAAUUGGUUACACUUGUUUUUCAAAGCUAUCCUUUGAGGAGAAAGUCAAAAUGUGUUGUUAGCCUACCUCCACUCAGGCCUCUUGCUGUGUAAUCAUUAUUCCAGGUUAUGAUGUGCAUAGCUUUUAAAACUGCGUGUACUAUUAUUCUGCUCUUUCCCAUACUCUUGUCAUGUAUUCAGAACCUAAACUUAUAGCAAAAGAGCCAAGCAGUAGCAGUUUUUGUAAAUGUAAAAAUAAUUAGAUCCAGACUUUGUUUCCUUCAAUUUUAAAAAUAAAAAAUACCUCAGUGCUAUGUUUUUCAGUUAUCACCUGCAUUUCUCAAAAAAUAACACCUGCUUCAUGUGGCACAUAACUUGUAAGAAUCACAUUUUGGAUUUUAAAGAAAGACUAUUAAAUAUUUUAAGAUCACUAUCAA